GAGAGAGAGAGAGAGAGAGAGAGAGAGAAACGUUUACUCUGGAAUGUAAAUCUCCGGUGAAGAAGAGGAAGAAUGCGAGCAAAUCUCUGGACGUUGCACUCAAGAACUGAAGAAUGUGGAUCCAGAUGGAAGGGUUCUAUAGUGUCCAGGACAAUAAAUGAAGAAAGACCCAGUCCAGGGCACAGGAUCAAGGCGAAUGCUGCAUCAGUGCCCAGGCAAGCCCAGGAGUUGACAUUUCUCUGCCCAGCCAUGGGCCUCACCCUGCUCUUGCUGCUGCUCCUGGGACUAGAAGGUCAGGGCAUAGUUGGCAGCCUCCCUGAGGUGCUGCAGGCACCCGUGGGAAGCUCCAUUCUGGUGCAGUGCCACUACAGGCUCCAGGAUGUCAAAGCUCAGAAGGUGUGGUGCCGGUUCUUGCCGGAGGGGUGCCAGCCCCUGGUGUCCUCAGCUGUGGAUCGCAGAGCUCCAGCGGGCAGGCGUACGUUUCUCACAGACCUGGGUGGGGGCCUGCUGCAGGUGGAAAUGGUUACCCUGCAGGAAGAGGAUGCUGGCGAGUAUGGCUGCAUGGUGGAUGGGGCCAGGGGGCCCCAGAUUUUGCACAGAGUCUCUCUGAACAUACUGCCCCCAGAGGAAGAAGAAGAGACCCAUAAGAUUGGCAGUCUGGCUGAGAACGCAUUCUCAGACCCUGCAGGCAGUGCCAACCCUUUGGAACCCAGCCAGGAUGAGAAGAGCAUCCCCUUGAUCUGGGGUGCUGUGCUCCUGGUAGGUCUGCUGGUGGCAGCGGUGGUGCUGUUUGCUGUGAUGGCCAAGAGGAAACAAGGGAACAGGCUUGGUGUCUGUGGCCGAUUCCUGAGCAGCAGAGUUUCAGGCAUGAAUCCCUCCUCAGUGGUCCACCACGUCAGUGACUCUGGACCGGCUGCUGAAUUGCCUUUGGAUGUACCACACAUUAGGCUUGACUCACCACCUUCAUUUGACAAUACCACCUACACCAGCCUACCUCUUGAUUCCCCAUCAGGAAAACCUUCACUCCCAGCUCCAUCCUCAUUGCCCCCUCUACCUCCUAAGGUCCUGGUCUGCUCCAAGCCUGUGACAUAUGCCACAGUAAUCUUCCCGGGAGGGAACAAGGGUGGAGGGACCUCGUGUGGGCCAGCCCAGAAUCCACCUAACAAUCAGACUCCAUCCAGCUAAGCUGCUCAUCACACUUUAAACUCAUGAGGACCAUCCCUAGGGGUUCUGUGCAUCCAUCCAGCCAGCUCAUGCCCUAGGAUCCUUAGGAUAUCUGAGCAACCAGGGACUUUAAGAUCUAAUCCAAUGUCCUAACUUUACUAGGGAAAGUGACGCUCAGACAUGACUGAGAUGUCUUGGGGAAGACCUCCCUGCACCCAACUCCCCCACUGGUUCUUCUACCAUUACACACUGGGCUAAAUAAACCCUAAUAAUGAUGUGCAAACUCUUAAUGGCUGAAUGGGAAAGGAAACUGCCCAAGUUUGACUAAUUGCUUGGCCUGUGAAUGGAAAAGACUCUGGUCUAAA